AUUUCUCCCCAGGGGGCUCUAGGCUGUGGAUGUGAGAAGGGGAGCAAGGGAGGCAGAUGGCGACAAGGAACAGCCCCAUGCCCCUGGGCACGGCUCAGGGUGACCCUGGAGAGGCAGGAACACGGCCCGGCCCUGACGCCAGCCUCCGGGACACAGGUGCGGCCACUCAGCUCAAGAUGAAGCCCAGGAAGGUGCACAAGAUCAAGGCGGUCAUCAUCGACCUGGGCUCCCAGUACUGCAAGUGCGGCUACGCGGGAGAGCCGAGGCCCACCUACUUCAUCUCCUCCACCGUGGGCAAACGCUGCCCCGAGGCGGCCGACGCUGGCGACACCCGCAAGUGGACUUUAGUGGGCCAUGAGCUGCUCAACACGGAGGCGCCUCUCAAGCUGGUGAACCCGCUGAAGCACGGCAUCGUGGUGGACUGGGACUGCGUGCAGGACAUCUGGGAGUACAUCUUCCGCACCGCCAUGAAGAUCCUCCCCGAGGAGCACGCUGUGCUGGUCUCCGACCCUCCGCUCAGCCCCAGCAGCAACCGGGAGAAGUACGCGGAGCUCAUGUUUGAGACCUUCGGCAUCCCAGCCAUGCACGUGACGUCCCAGUCGUUGCUGUCCAUCUACUCCUACGGCAAGACCUCGGGGCUGGUGGUGGAGAGCGGGCACGGCGUCUCGCACGUGGUGCCCAUAUCCGAGGGCGACGUGCUGCCGGGCCUGACCAGCCGCGCCGACUACGCUGGGGGUGACCUCACCAACUACCUGAUGCAGCUGCUCAAUGAGGCGGGCCACGCAUUCACGGACGACCACCUGCACAUCAUAGAGCACAUCAAGAAGAAGUGCUGCUAUGCGGCCUUCCUGCCCGAGGAGGAGCUGGGCCUGGUCCCGGAGGAGCUGCGCGUGGACUACGAGCUCCCGGACGGCAAACUCAUCACUAUUGGCCAGGAGCGCUUCCGUUGCUCUGAGAUGCUCUUCCAGCCCUCCCUGGCAGGCAGCACCCAGCCGGGCCUCCCGGAGCUCACAGCUGCCUGCCUGGGCCGCUGCCAGGACACGGGCUUCAAGGAGGAGAUGGCCGCCAACGUGCUACUGUGUGGCGGCUGCACUAUGCUGGAUGGCUUCCCCGAGCGCUUCCAGAGGGAGCUGAGCCUCCUCUGCCCCGGGGACAGCCCUGCAGUGGCUGCCGCUCCUGAGAGGAAGACCUCCGUGUGGACCGGCGGUUCCAUCCUGGCCUCCCUGCAGGCCUUCCAACAGCUCUGGGUCAGCAAGGAAGAGUUUGAGGAGCGGGGCAGCGUGGCCAUCUACAGCAAGUGCUGAGCCUCGGCAUUUCCACAGACAAGGCCUCCAGCACAGAUGGCCACAGGCCUCUCUAUACACAUUUACAGAAUUUCACAUAAAGGUUUACUCUGAAA